ACCGCAAAGAAGUCGCGCUUUGAUUGGGCCGCUGUCAGGUGUCGCUGCCUGCAGGUUCGGCUGCGCGAGCGGAGGGAGGCGGGACUCAAGAGUAGCCUUCCUCGAGGACCUGCCUUUCCCAUUUGCUGCCUGAAGUUAAUGUUUCUUGCUGGCCAAAUCAGGGACAUGCCGGCAUUAGCGGGAUGAGUGGGUGUUCCGGCAGGGAUGUGGUCAUUGACGGCCAGUGAGGGCGAGAGUACCACGGCCCACUUCUUCCUUGGAGCUGGAGAUGAGGGGCUGGGCACCCGUGGAAUAGGCAUGAGGCCAGAAGAGAGUGACAGCGAGCUCCUUGAGGAUGAGGAGGAUGAAGUGCCUCCUGAACCUCAGAUCAUUGUUGGCAUCUGUGCCAUGACCAAGAAAUCCAAGUCCAAGCCAAUGACUCAAAUCCUAGAGCGACUCUGCAGAUUUGACUACCUGACUGUUGUCAUUCUGGGAGAAGAUGUAAUCCUUAAUGAACCUGUGGAAAACUGGCCAUCCUGCCACUGCCUCAUCUCUUUCCACUCCAAAGGCUUUCCUCUGGACAAAGCUGUUGCUUACUCCAAGCUUCGAAACCCCUUUCUUAUCAAUGAUCUGGCCAUGCAGUAUUACAUCCAAGAUAGGAGGGAGGUGUACCGGAUCCUGCAGGAAGAGGGUAUUGAUCUGCCUCGAUAUGCUGUGCUCAACCGUGAUCCUGCCCGGCCUGAGGAAUGCAACCUGAUAGAAGGUGAAGACCAAGUAGAGGUCAAUGGAGCUGUCUUUCCCAAGCCCUUUGUGGAGAAGCCAGUGAGUGCAGAAGACCACAAUGUUUACAUCUACUACCCCAGCUCAGCUGGAGGAGGAAGCCAGCGUCUCUUUCGUAAGAUUGGCAGCCGAAGCAGUGUUUACUCUCCUGAGAGCAGCGUCCGAAAGACGGGGUCGUACAUCUAUGAGGAGUUUAUGCCAACAGAUGGCACAGAUGUCAAGGGUGAGCUGUGGGCAUACUCAGUGAUGCUAUGUACCUGCAGGUGUAUACAGUGGGGCCAGAUUAUGCCCAUGCUGAAGCUAGAAAAUCUCCAGCUUUGGAUGGGAAGGUUGAACGAGACAGUGAGGGGAAAGAGAUUCGAUAUCCAGUCAUGCUGACUGCCAUGGAAAAGCUGGUGGCCAGGAAAGUCUGCGUAGCUUUCAAGCAAACAGUUUGUGGAUUUGACCUUCUUCGUGCCAAUGGUCAUUCCUUUGUGUGUGAUGUCAAUGGCUUUAGUUUUGUCAAGAACUCGAUGAAAUACUACGAUGACUGUGCCAAGAUUCUGGGGAACACCAUAAUGCGGGAGCUUGCCCCACAGUUCCAGAUUCCAUGGUCCAUCCCCACGGAGGCUGAGGACAUUCCCAUUGUUCCCACCACAUCUGGCACUAUGAUGGAACUUCGUUGUGUCAUUGCAAUUAUUCGUCAUGGGGAUCGUACUCCCAAGCAGAAGAUGAAGAUGGAAGUGAAACACCCAAGGUUUUUUGCUCUGUUUGAAAAACAUGGUGGCUACAAGACAGGGAAAUUAAAACUCAAGCGACCUGAGCAGCUCCAGGAGGUGCUGGAUAUCACAAGGCUGUUGUUGGCUGAACUGGAGAAAGAACCAGGUGGUGAGAUCGAGGAGAAGACUGGAAAACUAGAGCAGCUGAAGUCUGUACUGGAGAUGUAUGGUCACUUCUCAGGUAUAAACCGGAAGGUACAAUUGACUUACUACCCUCAUGGAGUAAAAGCUUCUAAUGAGGGGCAAGAUCCACAGAGGGAAACUCUGGCCCCAUCUCUGUUGCUGGUACUGAAGUGGGGUGGAGAACUGACUCCUGCUGGCCGUGUUCAGGCUGAGGAGCUGGGGCGAGCUUUUCGCUGCAUGUACCCUGGAGGACAGGGUGACUAUGCUGGCUUCCCUGGUUGUGGGCUGCUUCGUCUCCAUAGCACUUUCCGCCACGAUCUCAAGAUCUAUGCCUCUGAUGAGGGUCGUGUUCAGAUGACUGCUGCUGCCUUCGCCAAGGGCCUUCUGGCUCUAGAAGGGGAGCUGACACCCAUUUUGGUGCAAAUGGUGAAGAGUGCCAACAUGAAUGGGCUACUGGACAGCGAUGGGGAUUCCUUGAGCAGCUGCCAGCACCGGGUGAAGGCUCGGCUGCACCAUAUUCUACAGCAGGAUGCGCCCUUUGGCCCUGAGGACUACGAUCAGUUCUGGGCUCAUCUGAUCUUGCUUGGAGUCUCUCCUGAAAUUGCAGUCAGAUAUUGACUGGAGCUGGAACCAUCUGGAAGUUCAGCUGGGACUGUGGGAUGGCUGGCUCUCUCCCUCUUCAUGCUCUCCCUGUAACCUCAGUGCCUCUUUUCUCCACAUGGUUCUUCAUAUGGUUUCCGUAGCAUGAUAGCCAGAAGUAUUAAAUGGUAGCUUUAGGGAUAUUCAAAAGCAGAAGCUUAGAAGCUUUCUUAAAGUGUAGGCCCAGAAAUAGCACAACAUAACUUUGUUAUUUUUUAUUGGUUAAACAGUUACAGGGCCAGCCAGAUUUAAGGGAAGGGAAGGAAAGGAAGACAAAGAAUUGAUGGUCAUCUUUAAAGCACUACAAGGACUGUAGACCACAAGGACUUUCCUCCCAUUUUACAGAUGAGGAAACCUAGGCUCAGAAGAAUCUAAGCAAUUUUCCUCAUGUCAUCCAGCUAAUACAAACCGAAGGGGUCUAACUCCAACGCCCAGGCUGUUACAUUGCUUUAUAGUAUUAAUCCCACUAUAUGCCAUUACCCAAUAUGGUCGUUCUUUUUCCUGCAUAUCUAGGCCACAAAUGACCAGGCAGUGGUUUUCUACUCUUCCCACUCCUCAUUUCUGAUAUGUUCUUUUAAAAAAAUGUUUAAAACUUUAAAAUUGUGGUACCAUUUUAACCAUUUUUAAGUUUACAGUUCAGUAGCAUUACAUGUAUUUACAUUGUUGUGUAACAUUUCUGAUUGGUUCUUAAAUGAGUUAAGUAGCUAAGCACAUUGCUGUGAGCCCAUAGGAUUUUCUGUGUUCUCUGAGUAGGACUUGAUAAGGAACAGGACCUUGCUCCUUUAUUUCCCAAUCCAUUGCUCACUGUCAAACUCAAAAAAGCUAAGGCAGCUUUCCUUUCUGCCUUGCCUUCUUUUGCGAGCAAGAAUGAAACUUGUGAGGACCUAAACAGAAUUGUGCAUUUUCAGCCACAGUCUUGAUUCUGCCUCCACAUUUCUCAUUGACUGUUACUGUCCUACAAGCCUGAGUCAGAACCCAGUUUUGAGGCAGCAUUUCUACUCUAGGCUCAGGCUAGCAUCUUGUUUAGAGGAAGAAGAUAAUGUUAUCUGUGAUCUCUACUCAUGAAAACAUUCUGUGGAGAUUUUGAGGGAUUUUGGUUCAAUCUUUAUUCUCCAGUAUUUUCCAUGUGUAUUCUAGAGCCCUCAAGAAAAGAACUUAGGUCUGUUUUAUUUUCUCUGGACUCUUAAAAUCAAUCCCUCUUAGACGACUAUAUGCUAGAGCAGUGCCCUUACCUGAAGGCCUAGAACUGCUAGUAUGCCCAGUAACCUAAGAAUGCUCACUGGAGUGAACCAACAUACAGAGCUGUAUUGUGAGUAGUCUCUGUGUAAUAAACUCACAGGAAUCUGGGCAAUUAGUGCCGAGCCUGUCUUGCUUUUCUUCUCUCUAUUCUUCAUAGCUGGCUCCCACCAGAAGUACUUCCCUGCUCAACUCCAUGACUAUCAUCCAGAAUCCUGUGAAGGUCUGUGAUCAGGUAUUUGCCCUGAUCGAAAACCUCACCCACCAGAUCCGGGAACGAAUGCAGGACCCCAGGUCUGUAGACCUGCAGCUCUACCACAGUGAGACACUAGAGCUAAUGCUACAGCGUUGGAGCAAGCUGGAGCGUGACUUUCGACAGAAGAGUGGGCGCUAUGAUAUCAGUAAGAUCCCUGACAUCUAUGACUGUGUCAAGUAUGAUGUGCAGCACAAUGGGAGUCUGGGACUUCAAGGCACAGCAGAGUUGCUCCGUCUCUCUAAGGCACUGGCUGAUGUGGUCAUUCCCCAGGAGUACGGGAUCAGUCGGGAGGAGAAACUGGAAAUUGCUGUGGGCUUCUGUCUUCCACUGUUGCGGAAGAUACUACUUGACCUGCAGAGAACCCACGAGGAUGAGUCUGUCAACAAGCUGCAUCCCCUGUACUCCCGAGGCGUGCUCUCCCCAGGUCGCCACGUUCGAACGCGUCUCUAUUUCACCAGUGAGAGCCAUGUCCACUCCCUGCUCAGUGUCUUCCGUUAUGGAGGACUUCUUGAUGAGACCCAGGAUGCACAAUGGCAGCGAGCUUUGGAUUAUCUUAGUGCCAUCUCAGAGCUUAACUACAUGACCCAGAUUGUCAUCAUGCUUUAUGAGGACAACACACAGGAUCCCUUAUCAGAGGAACGGUUCCAUGUGGAGCUACACUUCAGCCCCGGAGUGAAAGGUGUUGAGGAAGAAGGCAGUGCCCCGGCUGGCUGUGGAUUCCGUCCAGCCUCUUCUGAGAAUGAGGAGAUGAAAACCAACCAAGGCAGUAUGGAGAACCUGUGUCCAGGAAAGGCAUCAGAUGAACCAGACCGGGCAUUGCAGACUUCACCCCAGCCUCCUGAGGGCCCUGGCCUUCCGAGGAGAUCACCCCUCAUUCGUAACCGAAAAGCUGGUUCCAUGGAGGUACUUUCUGAGACUUCAUCCUCGAGGCCUGGUGGCUACCGGCUCUUUUCAUCUUCACGGCCACCCACAGAAAUGAAGCAGAGUGGCCUAGGCUCACAGUGCACAGGGCUGUUCAGCACCACAGUGCUGGGUGGCUCCUCCAGUGCCCCGAAUCUUCAGGACUACGCCCGCAGCCAUGGCAAAAAGCUACCACCUGCCAGUCUGAAGCACCGAGAUGAGCUCUUGUUUGUCCCGGCCGUAAAACGAUUUUCUGUGUCGUUUGCAAAGCAUCCGACUAACGGGUUUGAAGGGUGUUCCAUGGUGCCUACCAUCUACCCUCUGGAAACACUGCAUAAUGCCCUUUCCCUACGUCAAGUGAGUGAAUUCUUGAGUAGAGUCUGCCAGCGCCACACUGAUGCCCAGGCACAGGCAUCUGCAGCCCUCUUUGAUUCCAUGCACAGCAGCCAGGCCUCAGAUAACCCAUUUUCUCCACCACGUACUCUUCAUUCACCUCCCCUGCAACUCCAGCAGCGCUCUGAGAAGCCCCCUUGGUACAGCAGUGGCCCUUCUAGCACUGUGUCCAGUGCUGGUCCUUCUUCCCCUACUACAGUAGAUGGUAACUCCCAAUUUGGCUUCAGUGAUCAACCCUCCCUAAAUUCACACGUGGCUGAAGAACAUCAAGGCCUUGGGCUGCUCCAGGAGACCCCUGGGAGUGGAGCACAAGAGCUCUCCAUAGAAGGGGAGCAAGAGCUUUUUGAACCAAAUCAGUCCCCACAGGUGCCACCUAUGGAAACCAGCCAGCCAUACGAGGAGGUCAGCCAGCCAUGUCAGGAGGUCCCUGACAUCAGCCAGCCAUGCCAGGACAUUUCUGAGGCGCUCAGCCAGCCAUGUCAGAAGGUCCCUGACAUCAGCCAGCAAUGCCAGGAGAACCAUGACAAUGGUAACCACACAUGCCAGGAGGUCCCUCACAUCAGCCAGCCAUGCCAGAAGUCCAGCCAACUGUGCCAGAAAGUCUCUGAGGAAGUUUGCCAGCUAUGUCUGGAGAACUCCGAGGAGGUCAGCCAGCCAUGCCAGGGGGUCUCUGUGGAGGUUGGCAAGCUGGUCCAUAAGUUCCAUGUAGGGGUUGGUAGCUUGGUCCAGGAAACCCUUGUAGAAGUUGGCAGCCCAGCUGAAGAGAUCCCUGAGGAGGUCAUCCAGCCAUACCAGGAGUUCUCUGUGGAGGUUGGCAGGCUGGCCCAGGAGACUUCUGCGAUCAAUCUGUUAUCUCAGGGCAUCCCUGAGAUUGAUAAACCAUCCCAAGAGUUCCCUGAGGAGAUUGAUCUGCAGGCCCAGGAGGUCCCUGAGGAGAUAAAUUAGAAGUCCUGGGUGGUCCCUGAAGUGAUUGAUCAGCUGCCUGGAGAGGGUAUUCCUCAAGCCCAGCAUCCAUCUGGUGAUCCAAACCCUCAGAGCCAGUCUCUAGCCCAUGACCAGCACUCACCCCUUCCACCAGCAACAUGUGAUUAAUUUUCUCAUUAGUGGUAUCACACUAUACCAGCCAUUUGAGCCAGCAACCUUUUCUGUUGGCUAACUCACUGGCCAGCUCUCACCAGCGGUGUCUGGGGAAGUAGUUCUCUUUGUAUGAAGCAUACCUGUGCCAGAGCUGUGGUUGAGGAGGAGCCAGUUUUAGGUUCGAAGAAGCCAUUGGCUCCUCACUUAGCCAUUAGACUUGAAUAGGAUUUCCUUGGGGUGGGUUGGUCUGUCAUUACCCAGCCUUCUCUGAGCAUCCUAGGAAAUCACAGAUUGUUAAAGGAAAUGCCGCUUCACUGCUGAAGACACCAUCUGGCGACAGCAAAUGCAAAAGAGGGGACUCUAGGGUCUUCACUUUUCUGGGGAAAUGUUCACGACUUCUCAAGGUACGCUUAGACCAUAUGUGCAUUCAGGGGACUCUUGUCUUUGCCAGCACUCCUCAGGUGAGCCCGGGAUGGCUAUCUGAAAUGUCUGGAAAAUAGAGUCCCUUCCCCAAACAUCUGACAUGGCCACUAAAUCUUUAGACUUGCCUUAUAGAUCCUUCCAUAUCAUCCCCAAGUGCCCCUUCUGCCUCAGUCCUGUUCCUCUGGGCAAUAGCUCUAGGGAAAAGUAGGUAUUAGACUGCUGUGCAAAAUUCAGAGCAACUACUUAAAAUGCUCUAGAGGAUUCUUAGCCAGUCUGUGAAAGUGGGCCUCCUCUGUGGUGGGGCUGUUUGGCUUAGGAGAUGCUGUAGUAGUAGAGAUAAUCAGGUUCUAUUUUAAGCAAUCAGCAGAGAUCAAUAUUGUACAGAUACAAGCAAAGGUUUAAUAAAUAUAUAUAUAUAUAUUUAUUUCUGUAGUUGUGCCAGGGACAGACUGGCCAAAGACCAAACACUGCAGGGUCCCCAAGAAAUUUGUCCUUAUAUCAUUGUGUCUGAGGGCCAGAUAUGAUUAUGAAGCUUUUUCCAAAGAUCCAGGGAUGGGAAUGGGAGUGGGUAGGAGGGGUAAUGCGGUCAUUGGAGUCGGGGGCUGGAACAUUAUGAGUGCUCAAUAAAUAUAAACUAAUGAGAA